UUCUCAUCUCCUGACACUAUGUAUUUCAAUUACAAAAGUGUGUGUGGGAGCUGUGGAUUUGGCUCUUGCUAUGGUUGUGGGUAUGGCUGUAUACACAGCACCCACUGUGGCUGUAACGGUUAUUAUGGUUGUUAUGAAAAUAAAUAUUCUGUUAUAGAUGAUCUGAUAUUUUUUGCUUCUAAGAAAUGCCAUUGAGCAUUGUUUCUUAUUUAGUUUCUCAAAGAUCUGUUCUGCUUUAAUCACCUUCAAUCCU